GCAUUCCCCGCGCGGAGCCGAAGCAGCCGCAACGAGCCGGGAGCUGAGCCGCGCUGCGCUGCGGUGCGAAGAGCCGGGCGGCGGCCAGAGCCCUCCCCGCGCUGCCAGUGGGACGCGGAGCCAGGGAUCCCCGGCUUUGCCCCGGGGCUGGGGUGCAACAGACUCUUAACUUGGUCCUCGCGCCCCGCCAACCGCCCCCGGGCAGGAAACGCCCAGAACCACCACCGCGCCGCGCUCCACAAAAGCCCCGGGAGUUCCAAGACGGGAGGGAUCGGGCGCGCUCCAGAGGCAGGAGGGUCCCCCACACCCUCAGGCUCAUGCCCAGCUCCCCCAUCGGGCAGCCCCCAGCCCCAUGAGGACCCUCAGGCCGGGGCGAGAGCCCGGCACAGCCCGGACCGAAAUUUUGCCGCUGCCUUAGAGCGUUAGACAGGAUGUGGCUGGGCCGCCGGGCCCUGUGCGCUCUGGUCCUUCUGCUCGCCUGCGCCUCGCUGGGGCUCCUGUACGCGAGCACCCGGGACGCGCCCGGCCUCCGGCUACCUCUUGCGCCGUGGGCGCCCCCGCAAAGCCCCCGCAGGCCCGAGCUGCCAGAUCUUGCUCCUGAGCCCCGCUACGCACACAUCCCGGUCAGGAUCAAGGAGCAAGUAGUGGGGCUGCUGGCUUGGAACAACUGCAGUUGUGAGUCCAGUGGGGGGGGCCUCCCCCUCCCCUUCCAGAAACAAGUCCGAGCUAUUGACCUCACCAAGGCCUUUGACCCUGCAGAGCUGAGGGCUGCCUCUGCCACAAGAGAGCAGGAGUUCCAGGCCUUUCUGUCGAGGAGCCAGUCCCCAGCUGACCAGCUGCUCAUAGCCCCUGCCAACUCCCCGCUCCAGUACCCCCUACAGGGUGUGGAAGUUCAGCCCCUCAGGAGCAUCUUGGUGCCAGGGCUGAGCCUUCAGGCAGCUUCUGGUCAGGAGGUAUACCAGGUGAACCUGACUGCCUCCCUAGGCACCUGGGACGUGGCAGGGGAAGUGACUGGAGUUACUCUCACUGGAGAGGGUCAGGCAGAUCUCACCCUUGUCAGCCCAGGGCUGGACCAACUCAACAGGCAACUACAACUGGUCACUUACAGCAGCCGAAGCUACCAGACCAACACAGCAGACACAGUCCGGUUCUCCACCGAGGGACAUGAGGCUGCUUUCACUAUCCGCAUAAGACACCCGCCCAACCCUCGGCUGUACCCACCUGGGUCUCUACCCCAGGGAGCCCAGUACAACAUCAGCGCUCUAGUCACGAUUGCCACCAAGACCUUCCUCCGUUAUGAUCGGCUACGGGCUCUCAUCACCAGUAUCCGCCGCUUCUACCCAACGGUUACCGUGGUCAUCGCUGACGACAGCGACAAGCCAGAGCGCGUUAGUGGCCCCUACGUGGAACACUAUCUCAUGCCCUUCGGCAAGCUCCUGGCCUUUCGAAAGCACUCAAAAGUCUGGAGAAGAAUACAAGCUGAGAAGGGUCGGGGGAGAGAAAGAAAGGUGGCAGAGGGCCAUGUCCUAUUUCUGCAGCCUCCCCAACCACACACACCUUUCUGCCAGGGCUGGUUCGCAGGCCGGAACCUGGCCGUGUCUCAAGUAACCACCAAGUACGUGCUGUGGGUGGACGACGACUUCGUCUUCACGGCGCGGACGCGGCUGGAGAGGCUUGUGGACGUGCUGGAGCGGACGCCGCUGGACCUGGCCCGCCUGGAGGCAACCUCCCUCUCCCUGCAGGUGGGGGGCGCGGUGCGCGAGAUCUCCGGCUUUGCCACCACUUAUCGGCAGCUGCUGAGCGUGGAGCCCGGCGCCCCAGGCCUCGGGAACUGCCUCCGGCAAAGGCGCGGCUUCCACCACGAGCUCGUCGGCUUCCCAGGCUGCGUGGUCACCGACGGCGUGGUUAACUUCUUCCUGGCGCGGACUGACAAGGUGCGCGAGGUCGGUUUCGACCCCCGCCUCAGCCGCGUGGCUCAUCUGGAAUUCUUCUUGGAUGGGCUUGGUUCCCUUCGGGUUGGCUCCUGCUCCGACGUCGUGGUGGAUCAUGCAUCCAAACUGAAGCUGCCUUGGACAUCAAGGGAUGCCGGAGCAGAGACUUACGCCCGGUACCGUUACCCAGGAUCACUGGACGAGAGCCAGAUGGCCAAACACCGGCUGCUCUUCUUCAAACACCGGCUGCAGUGCAUGACCUCCCAGUGAUGGCCCGCUGGGGAUUUCUGACUGUCAGGCUGGGCCUGCCUCCUUGUCCCUGCCAGGAAUUUCCAACAAACCCCACCACCCUGUGAGCACUCUACUGGCUGUCCCUGAGCCUCUAGUUCCUCACUCUUCCUUUUCAGAACCUGAUGCCCAGUAGGGGUUGUCCUGGUGACACCCCUCCUUUUUCCAGUGCCCAGAGGCCUGGUGGAGCCAUAACCUCUCCCACAGCCAGUGCCAAGUCCUCCCCCUGCCCAUUCUCAUGGGGCAGGAAAUGGGGGGAUCACUUUCCAAGUGCCAAAGAGCCCAGAGGGACUCUAAGAACCUAAGGUGGAAACACUGUCCUCUCAUCUUGGGACCGAGGGGGUGGGGAAGUUCCCCAACACAUAAUCCCAAGACUGUGCCCCUCAUCUGCAUCUUCAGAUCCAGUACUCUGUGUACCUGCUCCAGCCCCACCCCCACAGAGAGAACUUGUGGCUCUGGGGCUGGGGUGAGGGCUGGUGGUUGGUGAAAGCCAUUCUUAGUUGUGUCUCUGCAAUGCUGUGGGCACAAAAGAAGGGGCACCAGAGUCCCUGUGCAAACACCUAGACUCACUUCAUGGAUUCCAAAGCUCUCAGCUUCAUUUUAUUAGUUACGUUAGGUAAGGGGGUUCAAGGGUCAUGGUCCUCAUCACACACAUGUCAUCAGGGCCCUCUGCACUCCACAUGAUGAGGUCAGACCCACACGGUGCAAAUCUUUGGGUCAGUGAGCUCCUGGAGAAGAGAGGAGACAUGUCAGGAAUAGAUUAGGCACCCCUCUUCCUUAAUGAAAUGUGGCAGUCCUCUCAGGGGUACCCCACCUACUUAGGGAUCUGAGUUCUUCAGUUCCUCACCCAUAGCUCAGCCCGGGCUCCCUGAUUUGGUCUUCAAUCUACUAUUCAUUCCGUCCCCACCCUUUUCUUCUUGAUCUUCCUCAGACCCUUUCCCAAACCCCUCUCCCUGGGUCUCCAGCCACUUACCCCUGCCUCACUUGCCGCAGCCCAGUGCCUCCUGGCUCCCGCUCCUGGUGCUACUGCCCCUUAACAGGCUCCCCAGGGCAUAAGCAGCUGCAUCCUGCACACUCACAAACAGCUGAUCUGGAGUCACCCUGUCCAGGAGUCCUACCCGGGUCAGUGUCCCCUGCACCAAGGCUAUGUGGGGAGGGUGUCAGACUCUGAGACCCUAAGUCCACACCGGGUCCUUUUCCCUACCGCAGGUGUCCAGUCAUUGCCCAGGCACUGGGCCCCGCUCUUCUCCACACAUCUCACCAUUACACUGAGCCAGGAGGAGGCGGAUCCUAGCAUCUCGACAUCGGCUGGCCAGCUGCAGGGAUGGGGCAAAGGGGUUAAGUCCCAGAUCAGAGGGUAUGAGUGAGAUGCUAAGGGGUUUCUCCUCAACCUACCCUCUCCCUCACCUGCACCACUUCUCUGGCCCCAGCAGCAUCUGCAAAGGUGACACCACUGAAGUCUAGGACCACCACCCUGACAGGCUCAGCAACUAGAAUGGGAGAAGACAGGAGUACCCAGGUGUCACCAUGCAACAUGCCCAAAUCUUCCUUCUUGUCACCCCAUCUCACCUGCAACCAUUGGGCCAUCUGGCUUUGAAGUCUCCUAUAAGUAAAGAAGGGCAGUCACCACUCCCGAAACACAGCAUGAACAUGCACCCCUUGAGCACAAGGAUCCCCCUCAGAACACCCACCUGCCUCCCACUCCCUGAGGAUCCACAUCCCUCCUAAACCAAGCUCCUUCACCUUUUCUCCUUCUCCGAGCCCCAGGUGCCACUCCAGGUUGCAGCGAAACUGCCCACGGGUCCCAAAGUACAGUGGUGUUGGAUAGCUCAGGAUGCAGAGCCCCGGGACCUGGAGGAGCUAAGAGGUCAAAGGAUCAGAGAAAUGUCUGGGGCUAAUCUUCCCUUCCUUCUUUGGCUGCAGCCCACCCACCCUGGGGCUUCCUCUGAGUGGUCUGUAGAGCUCUGUCCCCUCAGCCUGUCCAAGUGCCAGGCACUACACCCUAGGGAAGAAGGUGGGGCCAGAUUUCCAGCUUAGCCUGGCCUGGCUGGAGAGUCACCCCAAGCACCUCAUUCUCUUCCCCUGCCCCGACCUCAACUCCACUCAUCUCUAUGCCCACCUCCGGGUGCGGCAGACCACAGUCAUCAUGGAGAAGACCACACCCACAGCCAGGCCCAAAUCCACACUCAGGGUCACUACUGCCACCCAGGUGACCAUCCACACAGCCUGCAGGAUAGGGAUAGGGGUGGAUUGCCCAAAAGAAAAGCCAGGCCAUCACUGCUGGGUAAAGAGAUCCAGGGCAGUGACUACCAAGGCAAGUGAUGGGGAGAGAUGAUCCAGGAAGAAGUGGAAAGCAUGACAGAAGGAAACAACAGGGUUGAUUCAAUGGGACACACACCAAAUGUAAUGACCCGCACCAGUUGGGAAGUUACAAAUAUUCAGGCCAAAGGGGUUCAAACCCCAUCCUUUCCCUUGCCUGUGAGUAAAGCAUACUAGGAGUUAUGUUUGCUGGGGGAGUGGGUGGGUUGCAGAACUUAAGACCAGGACAAUUAGGUUUGGUUCAGGGCAGAGGCUGGGGAUGCUAACAAGAUGAGAGGGGGCAAUCUGGGGGUAAUGGCAUUUCUCACAAAGUCCACUCGGCUGAUGUGCCAUAGUUGUGGAAGUUCCUGCAUCUGGCAGAACACCUGGCGCAUGCUGGAGAUGUUGAUGCAAGCCAGGACAGCCUUGAGGCAGAGGAGGUGGGCUGACUACCUCGAUGUCCUGGAAUACAGCUACCCCUCCCAGCCAUGCUCAUGCCUCCUCUGCUCAUUACCUUGGGCAGAUAGUAAAAGAAGGGCCCCAGCCACAGCAGCACCGACAGGACCACUGUGCAGGAGAAGAGGCCUGCCAGCUAGAGAAAAGGAGGAACAGGAGCAAAAAAGGAAGAGAGCCUCCCACCCCCACAUGAGAGCUGGUCUUCCUGCCCACUCUGCCUAAUCUUCCUCGGAAGUCUCCCUUCUCCCAAAUCUCCUUCCACACAACCCCCUUCUUAAUAUUCUGCCAUUCACAUCUAACCCUCCCGCUCCCCCCAAUUAAUUAAAUGCCCAUUAUUCACCAGUCUCCUUGUAGAUGUCCAUUGUUCAAGUUCCCCAGUUUUGUAGCCCACCUCCACCUUAAAAGCCACUGUUGGGUUACCCUAUAAGCAGGGUAUAUGUGUUUAGGGCACCAGCAAAGUAAGGGAAACCAAAAAUAUUAGGGGGAGACUUUGAUAUGUGAUAUUCCUUUUAAAAGACAAUGUCAUUGUGUGAAAAAAAUAAGAAUUUUAUCUCUUAAGUUUA